GAUUGGGCCACUACACUCCAGUAUGGGUAACAGAGGGAGAUACUGUCUCAAAAAAAAAACACAAGAAAAAACUCACCUUUCCCUCACCCACUCUGUGUGAUUUCUUUAGGUAUUAGAAGGAAGUGAUCUAUUAUCUAAUUAAAGUAAUUUACAGUAGGAUAUGAUUAACUGCUGUGCUUAACGCUUUAGGCAACUCCAUAGGAAAAGAGAAGCUUGUUGACUUGAUACGUGAAUGUGGGGAUGGUGACACUUCACCUCUUUCUGCCAGGCUUUCCAGUUGCAGUCAUAGAAAAGCAAGAAACAGUGGCUUGCCAACUCAUUUCUGAAAAAUUGUUUUGAUUUAACCCAACUUUAAUUACAUUUUUUCCCACUACCCUUCUAUCACAGCAAUCUGAUUAACUUUUUCAUAGUGUUCUUUGGUGUGUUUCAAAUAAUAACAAAUCAUUUUAGUUUUAUAGACUAAGUAAACAAUUUUGGAGGCUCUAGUUGAAUCGCUGAUCAAUAGUUUGCAUAAUAAAUCUUGAUUGACUAAAAUUAAUAGCCUCAGAGUUUAUGGAUUUCUGUUUCUGGGGCUUUCCAAACUCCCCCCUGCCCCCUCACCCCGACUCUCACCCAGGCUGGAGUGCAGUGGCACAAUCUCAGUUCACCACUGCAACCUCCACCUCCCAGGUUCAAGCCCUCAGCCUCCCGAGUAGCUGGGAUUACAGGCACGUACCACCACACCCUGCUAAUUUUUGUAUUUUUAGUAGAGACAGGGUUUCUCCAUCUUGGCCAGGGUGGUCUUGAACUCCUGACCUCAAGUGAUCCGCCCUCCUCAGCCUCCCAAAGUGCUAGGAUUGCAGGCGUGAGCCACCACGCCCAGCCUCCCCUGGCCCCUGCCUUUUUUUUUUUUUUAACAUUCCCAGUAACAGUUAUUUAUUUUUCUGACUAGAUAAAUGAUCAGUAAAUAUUAUCUAUGUGAUUUAGAGAGUAGGAGUUUAGUGUGUAGAGUUUAAUAAGAUGAAAGUGUUCUUGGGGUCUUGUGAGACUAAUAGAACAAGAGUUACUACUGGUUCCACUGUGGAAAAAUUUAUAGGAACUGUAGUCUUUAUAAUAAUCCCUUUAAGGACAAAAUUCGUUUAUUGCCUGUCUUCUCACACUUCGGAGCAAAACUUAACUGAAUGAACCUUGAAGAUUGAGUUAAUCUUUUCUAGAAAAGAAUUAAAUUAGGAAGAAAACCUGCUAAAACUUUUGUCUGUCAGUCAGCAUUUAUUUGGCUCUCCUGUGGGUAGAUUUGUAAUGGAGAAACAGGAGCACUAGAAACCUUGCCUCAUUCUUGUUUCAGAGAAAACCUAAAAUCCCAGCUGGGAUCCAAAACCUGUAUGCACACAAAUAUCAGCAAAUCUUAAUGCUCUAGAGUACAGACUUCCUGACUUCAAAGUUGAUUCAUCAUAGCAAAAUUAAAACUAUAACUUGGCAAAAAAGUGAUCGACAUUCUAAAGAUUUGAAAGCAUUGGCUGGGUGCAGUGGCUCAUGCCUGUGAUGCCAGCACUUUGAGAGGCUGAGACGGGAGGAUCACUUGAGCCCAGGAGUUCAAGAACAGCCUGGGGAAUGUGGGGAAACCUCAUCUCUACAAAAAAAAUACAAAAAAUUAGGUGGGUUUGGUGGUGAGAGCCUGUAGUUCCAGCUACUCAGGAGGCUAAGGCGGGAGGAUCACUUGAGCCUGGGGAGGUCAAGGCCUGCAUGACAGAGCAAGACCCUGUCUCAAAAAAAAAAAAAAAAGAAAAAAGAAAAAAAAUUGAAAUCGUUAAACAAAAUUAUUUGUAACUUAAAUUGACUUUUCAAUACUCAAUUCAAAUUUGUAGGAUAGCAUCUUUAUCAUGAGGUAAGUCAGUAUUACAGUUCCUAAGCCUAAAUACUAUCAGUGCCUUUCGUUUAAAAUCUAGGUUUAUCUGGAACUUUUGGCAACAGUCUUCGUUACGGCAUAUUUACCUGCUGCUGUUUCAGUACUUGUCAGCAAAAAUCAAACCACCAGGGCUCCCUGUUUUUACCUCCCUCUGAGUCAUUUCCUCUCCAAUUCUCUCCUUUAAAUAUUAUUGCUUCAGUCUCCAGUUAGUUUCCUCUGUAUAUUAGUUGAGUGCUUCUGCUUGAAAACAAAAGUUUAAUUUUGUUUUUUAUUUUGUUAUUUUUAUGAACAUUUCUGUAUUUGAUUUUGUGAUCACGUUUCCGUUACCUUGAUUACUAAUAGAUCAGUGAUUUUUUUGCAGUCUAAUUAGUGAUCGUAUGUGUGACUAAAAGUAGGGGGAGGCUGGGUGCGGUGACGCACGCCUAUAAUCCCAGCACUUUGGGAGGCUGAAGUGGGUGGAUCAUGUAAGGUCAGAAGUUCAAGACCAGCCUGGCCAACAUGGUGAAACCCUGUCUCUACUAAAAAUGGAAAAGUUAGCCUGGCGUGGUGGCAGGCGUCUAUAAUCUCAGCUACUUGGGAGGCUGAGGCAGGAGAAUCGCUUAAACAUAGGAGGCAGAGGUUGCAGAGAGCUGAGAUUGUGCCAUUGCACUCCAACCUGGGCGACAGAGCAAGACUCCGUCUCAAAAAAAAAAAAAAGCUUUGUGUUGGGAAUGGAAACUUUGGGCAGAUUGCCAGAUUAUUUUAAAUGAUUUUAUCUCUGUACCACUGGGCUAAAUUCAAGUAUCUUAUCUGAAAAUAGCACAACAGCUCUGGGGGCUGGCACUCGGGUAAGCUCUCCUUUCGCUUAUGAAAUGAAAAAUUAAAUUUGUCCAGGUAGAUUUAUUUGCUUCCUUUUGUCUUGACCAAGAUUAGAGUUGUAUAAAUUGCCCUGAUUUCCUUUUUGCCUUGACCAGCAGGCGGGCACGGCAGGCCGGUAUUAUGUGGCAUUUCCAGUGUGUGUAUAUCUGGGAUUCCUAGAGGAUGAGAAAUCUAAAUUUUACACUGUUGUAGUCUCCGGGACCAUUAUGGCAGUCAAGUGGACGGGUGGGCAUUCUUCUCCUGUCCUCUGCCUGAAUGCAAGUAAAGAAGGGCUGCUGGCUUCUGGAGCAGAGGGCGGAGAUCUCACGGCUUGGGGUGAAGAUGGAACUCCAUUAGGACACACGCGGUUCCAAGGGGCUGAUGAUGUUACCAGUGUCUUAUUUUCUCCCUCCUGUCCCACCAAGCUCUAUGCCUCACAUGGAGAAACCAUUAGUGUACUGGAUGUCAGGUCCCUCAAAGAUUCCUUGGACCAUUUUCAUGUGAAUGAAGAAGAAAUCAAUUGUCUUUCAUUGAAUCAAACGGAAAACCUGCUGGCUUCUGCUGACGACUCUGGGGCAAUCAAAAUCCUAGACUUGGAAAACAAGAAAGUUAUCAGAUCCUUGAAGAGACAUUCCAAUAUCUGCUCCUCAGUGGCUUUUCGGCCUCAGAGGCCUCAGAGCCUGGUGUCAUGUGGACUGGAUAUGCAGGUGAUGCUGUGGAGUCUUCAAAAAGCCCGACCACUCUGGAUUACAAAUUUACAGGAGGAUGAAACAGAAGAAAUGGAAGGCCCACAGUCACCUGGUCAGCUCUUAAACCCUGCCCUAGCCCAUUCUAUCUCUGUGGCUUCGUGUGGUAAUAUUUUUAGUUGUGGUGCAGAAGAUGGUAAGGUUCGAAUCUUUCGGGUGAUGGGAGUUAAGUGUGAACAGGAACUGGGAUUUAAGGGCCACACUUCAGGGGUAUCCCAGGUCUGCUUUCUCCCAGAAUCCUAUUUGCUGCUUACUGGAGGGAAUGAUGGGAAGAUCACGUUGUGGGAUGCAAACAGUGAAGUUGAGAAAAAACAGAAGAGUCCCACAAAACGUACCCACAGGAAGAAACCUAAAAGAGGAACUUGCACCAAGCAGGGUGGAAAUACUAACGCUUCAGUAACAGAUGAGGAAGAACAUGGCAACAUUUUACCAAAGCUAAAUAUUGAACAUGGAGAAAAAGUGAACUGGCUCUUGGGUACAAAAAUAAAGGGACACCAAAAUAUAUUAGUAGCUGAUCAAACUAGUUGUAUAUCUGUAUACCCCUUAAAUGAAUUUUAAAUCCAAUAAAAACAUUUGAAGAAUUGUGGCAAAA